AUUUUCCUCUGCUUCUCUCAGGGCAGCUGGCGUGGCCACCUCGCAAGGCUGCUUCUAGGGACACGAGACUCGGGAGGGUCAGAGACUUUCAGGCCGGGCCUUCACUCCCUUCCCCGGGGCACUUGGGCAAGAGUUCCAGCUCUUGGCUACCUCUGGCCCGCGCGUGAGUUCAGACACCCAGCACACGCGACCCCCGCAGGGAAACCCCGGGAAGCUGCGCGCAAUCGCUGGGGACUCGCCAGGGCUCCACUUCCCAAGCUCCGCGCCCCCUGCGCCCAAAGAGGCAGGGCGGAGCAGAGGCCGCCGGCGUGGAGGAGGCGAGCGCGGGGCUGGCCCGGGAGCCGCCCCCGGGGAGGGACUGAGACCUGCCCCAGGAGUCGAGGGCGAGCGGCGGACCCGGCUGGGCCCGGCGCACGCCGAGGAGAGGGAGCCCCCGCCACCGCCGCUGCCUCCGCGUGCUCAGCCUGUCCCCGCCCAGGGAGCCGGAGCCUCCAACUAACUCCGCCCGCCGCUCCGCCGCCCGCAGGCUCCGGCUUCCGUCCCGGACAGAGCCCGUGGUCGCGCAGGUUCUGAAUGAUGACUGACGCGGGUUUGGGUGAUACCCCUCACAGCCCCUGUCAUUCCGGAGUCAUAAGGCACCCGCGCGUCUAGCCCCAGCGCCAGGGCACGCGAGCGGCGCUGGAGGGAGGAAAGCUUCCGCCUGCGGGCCGGACAAAAGUCCCGCCUGCCCACGGCUUUUUGCCCGCCGCUCGUGACCGAGACGCCUCGCCGCGGCCAGCUCGCUGCUCUCGCUGGCGGAUGGUGUGUGGCCGCCGCAGGACGCCCGCCGUGCCCGGGCCAUGAAGUAGCGGCUGCUGGCGGCGCCGCUGCCCAACCGCCAGCCCCAGCCCCGCGCUGCGCUGCCCGGUCCUCUCCCGGCGGGGUCGUAUCGGCGUGGACAUGGCUGGCCGCGUCCCUAGCCUGCUAGUUCUCCUUGUUUUUCCAAGCAGCUGUUUGGCUUUCCGAAGCCCACUUUCUGUCUUUAAGAGGUUUAAAGAAACUACCAGACCAUUUUCCAAUGAAUGUCUUGGUACCACCAGACCCGUAGUUCCUAUUGAUUCAUCAGAUUUUGCAUUGGAUAUUCGCAUGCCUGGGGUUACACCUAAACAGUCCGAUACAUACUUCUGCAUGUCUAUGCGAAUACCAGUGGAUGAGGAAGCCUUCGUGAUUGACUUCAAGCCUCGAGCCAGCAUGGAUACUGUCCAUCACAUGUUACUUUUUGGAUGCAAUAUGCCUUCAUCCACUGGAAGUUACUGGUUUUGUGAUGAAGGAACCUGUACAGAUAAAGCCAAUAUUCUGUAUGCCUGGGCGAGAAAUGCUCCCCCUACCCGGCUCCCCAAAGGUGUUGGAUUCAGAGUUGGAGGAGAGACUGGAAGUAAAUACUUUGUACUACAGGUACACUAUGGGGAUAUUAGUGCUUUUAGAGAUAAUAACAAGGACUGUUCUGGUGUGUCCUUACACCUCACACGUCUGCCACAGCCUUUAAUUGCUGGCAUGUACCUUAUGAUGUCUGUUGACACUGUUAUCCCAGCAGGAGAAAAAGUGGUGAAUUCUGACAUUUCAUGCCAUUAUAAAAAUUAUCCAAUGCAUGUCUUUGCCUAUAGAGUUCACACUCACCAUUUAGGUAAGGUAGUAAGUGGAUACAGAGUAAGAAAUGGACAGUGGACACUGAUUGGACGGCAGAGCCCUCAGCUGCCACAGGCUUUCUACCCUGUGGGGCAUCCAGUUGAUGUAAGUUUUGGUGACCUACUGGCUGCAAGAUGUGUAUUCACUGGUGAAGGAAGGACAGAAGCCACACACAUUGGUGGCACGUCUAGUGAUGAAAUGUGCAACUUAUACAUUAUGUAUUACAUGGAAGCCAAGCAUGCAGUUUCUUUCAUGACCUGUACCCAGAAUGUAGCUCCAGAUAUGUUCAGAACCAUACCACCAGAGGCCAACAUUCCAAUUCCCGUGAAGUCUGAUAUGGUUAUGAUGCAUGAACAUCAUAAAGAAACAGAAUAUAAAGAUAAGAUUCCUUUACUACAGCAGCCAAAACGAGAAGAAGAAGAAGUGUUAGACCAGGGUGAUUUCUAUUCACUACUUUCCAAGCUGCUAGGAGAAAGGGAAGAUGUUGUUCAUGUGCACAAAUAUAAUCCUACAGAAAAGGCAGAAUCAGAGUCAGACCUGGUAGCUGAGAUUGCAAAUGUAGUCCAAAAAAAGGAUCUUGGUCGAUCUGAUGCCAGAGAGGGUGCAGAACAUGAGAGGGGUAAUGCUAUUCUUGUCAGAGACAGAAUUCACAAAUUCCACAGACUAGUAUCUACCUUGAGGCCACCAGAGAGCAGAGUUUUCUCAUUACAGCAGCCCCCACCUGGUGAAGGCACCUGGGAACCAGAACACACAGGAGCUAGAAGAGAAGAUAUGAAAUGUUUCCAGUGCAAAGAAAUGAUAAGUGUUCAAGAUUUCCACAUGGAAGAGGCACUGGAUUGGCCUGGAGUAUACUUGUUACCAGGCCAGGUUUCUGGGGUGGCUCUAGACCCUAAGAAUAACCUGGUGAUUUUCCACAGAGGUGACCAUGUCUGGGAUGGAAACUCGUUUGACAGCAAGUUUGUUUACCAGCAAAUAGGACUCGGACCAAUUGAAGAAGACACUAUUCUUGUCAUAGAUCCAAAUAAUGCUGCAGUACUCCAGUCCAGUGGAAAAAAUCUGUUUUACUUGCCACAUGGCUUGAGUAUAGAUAAAGAUGGGAAUUAUUGGGUCACAGACGUGGCUCUCCAUCAGGUGUUCAAACUGGAUCCAAACAAUAAAGAAGGCCCUGUAUUAAUCCUGGGAAGGAGCAUGCAACCAGGCAGUGACCAGAAUCACUUCUGUCAACCCACUGAUGUGGCUGUGGAUCCAGGCACUGGAGCCAUUUAUGUAUCAGAUGGUUACUGCAACAGCAGGAUUGUGCAGUUUUCACCAAGUGGAAAGUUCAUCACACAGUGGGGAGAAGAGUCUUCAGGGAGCAGUCCUCUGCCAGGCCAGUUCACUGUUCCUCACAGCUUGGCUCUUGUGCCUCUUUUGGGCCAAUUAUGUGUGGCAGACCGGGAAAAUGGUCGGAUCCAGUGUUUUAAAACUGACACCAAAGAAUUUGUGAGAGAGAUUAAGCAUUCAUCAUUUGGAAGAAAUGUAUUUGCAAUUUCAUAUAUACCAGGCUUGCUCUUUGCAGUGAAUGGGAAGCCUCAUUUUGGGGACCAAGAACCUGUACAAGGAUUUGUGAUGAACUUUUCCAAUGGGGAAAUUAUAGACAUCUUCAAGCCAGUGCGCAAGCACUUUGAUAUGCCUCAUGAUAUUGUUGCAUCUGAAGAUGGGACUGUGUACAUUGGAGAUGCUCAUACCAACACCGUGUGGAAGUUCACCUUGACUGAGAAAUUGGAACAUCGAUCAGUUAAAAAGGCUGGCAUUGAGGUCCAGGAAAUCAAAGAAGCCGAGGCAGUUGUUGAAACCAAAAUGGAGAACAAACCCACCUCCUCAGAAUUGCAGAAGAUGCAAGAGAAACAGAAACUGAUCAAAGAGCCAGGCUCGGGAGUGCCUGUUGUUCUCAUUACAACCCUUCUGGUUAUUCCGGUGGUUGUCCUGCUGGCCAUUGCCAUAUUUAUUCGGUGGAAAAAAUCAAGGGCCUUUGGAGCAGAUUCUGAACACAAACUCGAGACGAGUUCAGGAAGAGUACUGGGAAGAUUUAGAGGAAAGGGAAGUGGAGGCUUAAACCUUGGUAAUUUCUUUGCAAGCCGUAAGGGCUACAGUCGAAAAGGGUUUGACCGGCUUAGCACUGAGGGCAGUGACCAAGAGAAAGAGGAUGAUGGAAGUGAAUCAGAAGAGGAGUAUUCAGCACCUCUGCCUGCGCUCGCACCUUCCUCCUCCUGAAAACCAAGCUUUGAUUUAGAUUGAGUAAGAUUUACCCAGAAUGUCAGAUUCCUUUCCCUUUAGCACGUUUAAAGUUCUGUGUAUUUAAUUGUAAACUGUACUAGUCUGUGUGGGACUGUACACACUUUAUUUACUUCGUUUUGGUUAAGUUGGCUUCUGUUUCUAGUUGAGGAGUUUCCUAAAAGUUCAUAACAGUGCCAUUGUCUUUAUAUGAACAUAGACUAGAGAAACCGUCCUCUUUUUCCAUCAUAAUUCUAAUCUAACAAUGGAAGAUUUGCCCAUUUACACUUUUGAGACUUUUUGGUGGAUGUAAAUAACCCCAUUCUUUGCUUGAACACAGUAUUUUCCCAAUAGCACUUUCAUUGCCAGUGUCUUUCUUUGGUGCCUUUCCUGUUCAGCAUUCUUAGCCUGUGGCAGUAAAGAGAAACUUUGUGCUACAUGACGACAAAGCUGCUAAAUCUCCUAUUUUUUUAAAAUCACUAACAUUAUAUUGCAAUGAAGGAAAUAAAAAAGUCUCUAUUUAAAUUCUUUUUUAAAUUUUCUUCAGUUGGUGUGUUUUUGGGAUGUCUUAUUUUUAGAUGGUUACACUGUUAGAACACUAUUUUCAGAAUCUGAAUGUAAUUUGUGUAAUAAAGUGUUUUCAGAGCAUUAGCUGUCAGUGUAUUUUCCAGUUUUUGCGUAUUUGCAGAUUUUACAUACAACUUUUAUAAUAAUUACACAAACCCACAAAUAUUAGUGAAACUUACUCGAUGUCUUCAACUAAAAGAAAUGUGUGUAUUGUACAAAAUUUAGAAGAUACUUUAGCCAAUAUAAAUUAAAAACCAGCCUGAGUUUACAUAAAUUUGUAAAGUCAGGCUCUUCUAAAAUCCAAAGAGGGUUUUUGCCUAUAUAUCAAUCAGAGGAUAAAUACUUUAAUAAAAGGUAAUCACAGCUAAGUGGAUACCUGUGUCUCAAAUUACAUAUGCAAAUGAUCCAUCAGUAGGGAUCACUAAUAAUAGUUUUCCUUUUAAAAAAUAAUUUCAGGGCAGGUACAGUGGCUCAAGCCUAUACUUCCAGGACUUUGGGAGGCCAAGCAGAAGGAUUGUGGGAGGCCAAGCAGAAGGAUUGUUUGAGCCCAGAAAUUCAAGGCUGCAGUGAGCUAUGAUCAAUCCACUGUACUCCAGCCUAGGCUACAGAGUGAGAUCCUUUCUCUAAAAUAAAAUACAAUUUCCAUGUAUCCAUAGGAAUAUAUUCAUCUUUUACAGUGAUUGCAGAUUAGUUUUAAAACGUCUUUUUCGUAAUUCGUCAAUGCAAGUUAGUAAGAACCAGAUAAUUUUCCAUUUUAAAAUGAUAGGAAUCUAAAACUCUUUUUCAAAAAUGCCAACCUGUUUUUCCGGCAUCAUAGUAGUUGGAAUAAUACAGAUAUAAUUGACUAAUCAUAAAGUACAUGAGAGUACAGAAGGGAAAUUUGGAAACGGUAAGUCUGCUAGGGCAUUACAAUCCUGUCCUAGCACUCCACCUUUAUUCUGCCAACCUGGGUUAAUUAAAGAUGGUAGCCUGGAAAGUAAUGAAUGACAUUGACUUCAGGCAAUCUUUCCACUGAUUAUUCUUGGCUGAACUUCAUUUAUCGAGUCAGAGAAUGCACUGCCUGAGAAAUGUCCCAGAGGAGUGAAUCCUAGGCCUGGCCACAGUAGAAUCGCCUGGAGAAUUUAAGAAAAAAAUUGUUGGGCACUCACUCUUUCCAGUGAUCUUUAUUUAGUUGGCUUACAAUGGAAUACAGGUAUGGUUCAUGUUUUUAAAUUUGUCCAGGUGUUUCUAUUGUGCAGUCACAGUUGAAAACCAUUGUCUUCGAGAAUAGCUAUUCUAUCUUGCCAGUUACAAUAAGUGGAUAGCUAUAUUUUCACAUAAAUUAUAGUUUACAGAUGUUUGGAGGGGGAAGACAGGAUCUGAGGUGUUUUGAUAUGACUGUUAGCACCAAAAUCUGAAUGCCUUAAUUGUUGAAUGUGUUAAAUUGGAUAAUUAAAAUGGGCAUAAAUGACUUAUUAAAAAAGCAAAGGGAAA